GUCAGAAGGAGGCGUCUGCGCUGAUCGGGUCCGCCGCGCGCCAGAGCCAGAGUCGCAGCCGAGGGGAGCCGGGGCCGGAGCCCGAGCCCGAGCCGAGCCGGAGCCCGAGCGAGCGGCGGAGACCGUGCCCCCGCCUCGGCCCCGCGCCGCCGCGGCCAGGCCCGGCAUGGAGGAGGAGUGCCGGGUGCUCUCCAUACAGAGCCACGUCAUCCGCGGCUACGUGGGCAACCGGGCGGCCACGUUCCCGCUGCAGGUUUUGGGAUUUGAGAUUGACGCGGUGAACUCUGUCCAGUUUUCAAACCACACAGCCUUAACCCCAGCACCUCAGUGUGGGACUGGGUUUGGAGAUGGAGCCCCUACAGAGGUCAGCAGGUUAAAAGAGGCCAUCAGGGCUCUGGGUGGGCCCUGAUCCAAGCUGCUUGGUGUCCUUGUAAGAAGAAGAGAUGAGGACACAGACACACACAGAGGGACAGCCCCAUGAGGAAACAGGGAGGCAAUGCCGUCUGCAAGCCCAGGGCAGAGGCCUCAGGAACCAGCCCUGGUGACACCUGGACCUUGGACCCCCGUGCCCAGGACAGUAGGAGAAUUGGAGCCGCCUGGCUGCAGUCCUUCCCGAUGGCACCCUGUAUUAGUCCGUUCUCACACUGCUAAUUGUUGGGAAAAGGGCUUGUGGAAUGCCUGUAUAAACUGGCCAUGAAAAUAUGGGACAAUAAGUUGUGGAAAGCCACAAGAGGCCUCUGAGGAGGAAAGCCUCCUAAUUGCCAUCAUGUUCGCAUGCUCAGGGCGAGACCUGCUGUCUUAUCUGUAAACACCGUGUUCAAGGAGAAAGACAUUCCUUCGAAGCACUGGACUGUGGACAGACACACGAGCUCCUGGUUAAGCCCGCUCCCACCAGCUCCUGUCCGAUAAGUUAAAGAUACGCUGUUUGAGCACAAAGGAGAUUCAUUGAAACCGCUAUUGCUGUAGAUUACGCCUGUGACGCACUGCCUCCCUUUCACUGUUUCGCCCUGAAUAUCUGCUUCUCAGAUCUAAGUGACUGUACUCAAUAAAUAGCGUGGAGACCAGAGCUCAGUGCCUUUUGCAGCCUCCAUUUUGCCACUGGCCCCCUGGCUCCUACCUUUAUGAACUCUUUUCUUUUUCUUUUUUUUUUUUUUUGGAGACGGAGUCUCACUCUGUUGCCCAGGCUGGAGUGCAGUGGCGCGAUCUCCACUCACUGCAAGCUCCACCCCCUGGGUUCAUGCCAUUCUCCUGCCUUAGCCUCCCAAGUAGCUGGGACUACAGGCACCCGCAACCACGCCCGGCUAAUUUUUUUGUAUUUUUAGUAGGGACGGGGUUUCACAGUGUUCACCAGGUUGGUCUCGAUCUCCUGACCUCACACACCACGCCCAGCUAAUUUUUGUAUUUUUUAGUAGAGAUGAGGUUUUGCCACGUUGGCCAGGCUGGUCUCGAACUCCCGACCUCAGGUGAUCUGCCUGCCUGAGCCUCCCAAACUGCUGGGAUUACAGGCGUGAGCCACCGCACCCGGCCCCACCUUUAUGAACUCUUAACCUGUCUCUUCUCAUUCCUUUGUCACUACCGGACGUUGGAUACACCAUGGGUGGUGUUGAGGCUGGUCCCCAACACUAAUAAAGACAUACCUGAGACUGGGUCAUUUGUAAAGGAAAAAGGUUUAAUGGACUCACAGUUCAGCAGAGCUGGGGAGGCCUCAGGAAACUUACAGUUAUGGCAGAAGGGGAAACAAACACCUCCUUCACAUUGGCGGCAGGAAGGAGAAGUGCAGACUGAGGGGCCCAGGGUUUUAAAAGCCCCUUGAAACCAUCAGCUUUUGUGAGAACUCAGUCACUAUCAUGAGAACAAGAUGGGGGAACCACCCCCAUGAUUGAAUGACCUCCUGCCAGGUCCCUCCCACAACAUGUAGGGAUUAUGGGAACUGCAAUUCAAGAUGAGAUUUGGGUGGGGACACAGCCAGGCCAUGUCACCUCCCCAGGAAAGGAGCACAUGUGCAGCAGUGGUGAGUCCCACCCUGCCUGGAAAGAUAUCAAAAUCCGAGGGCAGAAAGGACCAGGAGGGACCAUUGCUCACCUCCCUCCUCCUACCCCUUACCCCAAACCCCGCCCCAGCCUGGCAGAAGCCUCCUCAGGACACACCCUCCACCGGAGGGGCAGGCUGCUGUGUGAGGCACUGACCUCGCCCGCAGUGGAUACCACCUGCCCCUCCUGACCCCAGUGACUGUUAACCCAGAGUCCAUCAGGGGCUUGGUCUCUGGCAGACCCACCCCUCAGUGCGUACACUCUGGUGUCCCGGGCAGAGUACAGGGCAGGCGCCCCCAGGUGCACCCCCCAGAUGCCGCACUGUGCCUGGAGCGUGGCUCCUGAUGGCAGUCUCAGGACCUUUGCGCCACACGUCCUCCCGUGCGACGGCUGCUGGGGAAAGCCAAAGGCGUCCCUUCCAGCGGGAGCCAGCGACUGGUACGCAGGAGGGCCCUCAGGGGCAGGAGCCAUGGAGCCCUCCUCUGGUGUGGGAAUUCAGGGGAUCUUAGCCACAGGGCAUGGCGCGUGGGCGCAGAGCCGGCCGUGACCCACAAGUGCGUGAUACUUGUACUUUGCUAUUCUAGGAACCCAUACAUCAGUUUUCCUUAUUUGCUGAAAAAGGCAUGCAUUAGAGGGGUGAUUCAUGUGGGAGGAGGCCGGGAGCCCCUCGAUGUGAGGCGUUUCUCAUGGGCGAAUGUGGGGUAUCCAUGGUGGACCCCCACCCUGUGUGGAUGGCUGCCCCCUGAGCAGUGCUUUGAGCUGGAGCUGUGGUCAGGUUCCGCAGUGCAGGAAGGGCUCCCAGGAGGCUGGUGGUCCCGCCUGCAGGAAGCCGACGCGUCUGUCCUCACACAUUGAUAUGCCUGUCUGCCUGGGACGGACACUUCACCCUGGCUACCCAUCGGGCCAAGGGCAGGUUGUAUACACCUGGGCUGAGGCCUCUUUCUCAUUCACAUCUAUCUCUUGCUCAGGAGUUGAUCUAAGACAGGCUCUAAUUGCACCUUAAUAAGCUUGUUGGGGAGGAGUUGGGGGUGGGGACAUAACAAGCCCUACCUGCCAGGGUAUCCGGGUGACAGUGGCCGGUGGCCGAGCACCCCGGCCUGAAUAGCUGGGGACUAAUGCAGGAGACGCUGGGAAACAAGAGACUGUGACGUUGUGCGGAGGGAGUAGCCAGGGGCCUUCCGGACAGCAAUGGGGGAGCAACGCAGCCGUGAGCUGGCUAUGCCCACUGGAAGGGCCAAGUGCUGAAUUCAGAUGAGCUCCAGGAGUUGUACGAAGGCCUGAGGCUGAACAACAUGAAUAAAUAUGACUACGUGCUCACAGGUUAUACGAGGGACAAGUCGUUCCUGGCCAUGGUGGUGGACAUUGUGCAGGAGCUGAAGCAGCAGAACCCCAGGCUGGUGUACGUGUGUGAUCCAGUCUUGGGUGACAAGUGGGACGGCGAAGGCUCGAUGUACGUCCCGGAGGACCUCCUUCCCGUCUACAAAGAAAAAGUGGUGCCGCUUGCAGACAUUAUCACGCCCAACCAGUUUGAGGCCGAGUUACUGAGUGGCCGGAAGAUCCACAGCCAGGAGGAAGCCUUGCGGGUGAUGGACAUGCUGCACUCUAUGGGCCCCGACACCGUGGUCAUCACCAGCUCCGACCUGCCCUCCCCGCAGGGCAGCAACUACCUGAUUGUGCUGGGGAGUCAGAGGAGGAGGAAUCCCGCUGGCUCCGUGGUGAUGGAACGCAUCCGGAUGGACAUUCGCAAAGUGGACGCCGUCUUUGUGGGCACUGGGGACCUGUUUGCUGCCAUGCUCCUGGCGUGGACACACAAGCACCCCAAUAACCUCAAGGUGGCCUGUGAGAAGACCGUGUCUACCUUGCACCACGUUCUGCAGAGGACCAUCCAGUGUGCAAAAGCCCAGGCCGGGGAAGGAGUGAGGCCCAGCCCCAUGCAGCUGGAGCUGCGGAUGGUGCAGAGCAAAAGGGACAUCGAGGACCCAGAGAUCGUCGUCCAGGCCACGGUGCUGUGAGGGCCCCGCCGCUUGCCCGUGACACGCAGCGCGUUGGUGUCUCCGUGUUUGUCCCUGUGAAAACAUGUAACGUCUGCCUUAGAGCCAUGACCGAAACUUGAUAUUUUUUUCUUUCAUGAGUGUCCGGCAUCUGCUGGUCUUCAUUGUGAAACGUGCCAGUCGUGCUUUGUGAAAAAUAACAAAGUGGUCACAGAAAUUUGUGAUCUGAAAACCCGGCUCCCUUCCCCACAAGGCUCCUGGGCCUCCGGGAAGACGGGCCCCUGUUUGCCAUCUCGGGGGUGUUCCCUGUGGGAGGGUGAGUGGGUGAGGCCGAGCCUGCUGCGUGUGGAGCCUCGAGUGGGCCCUGGCUGCCACUACCGUACAGAGGCCGUGUCGCGCUGGGCUGGGCCUGGGUGGCCUCUGUCUUUGCAUCUCUGAGAAGGAGUCGGGUGGUAACGGUUGGGGUCAGGAAGAAUUCUGCCAAGUAUCUUUACUGUCAUUCUGACCAUAGCCUCUUUGUUCCCGCAUUCGAACUUUUGGUUCUUACUUUGCUGCUCGUUUAGUCCCUGGGGAUUUCAGAUCUUAGGCUGUUGUUUCACCGUAUGGGAGGGUUGAUGUGAGCUUGCUUGGAGACACACGGUGCAGCAUCAGGGACCUUCCCAGGCCCCAGCAAAUUCAAGUCGGUCUGCAGACCUCUCAGCUACCCGCGGGACCUCUUGUAACCCAUCGGCAUCUUCCAGGAAUCCGCCGAGUGACUUGAGGAAGAUGCUAACGCAGUAAGGUCUGUGCUGGGCCAAGAGCAGCUUUGAAGCUCCAGAGAACCACCCCGUCAGGUUCCUUGUGGAAGCUCCCCUCAUCCGUGGUGCAGCAGGCUGAGCACUGCGCGUUUGCCACGUGCUGCCCGUGACAGCACAUUGAGCCACAGCAUUUGUAGACAGGACAGAGGGGUGCCUGCCCCCUGCCCCUGCUGGCACAUUUAACCCUUGUCCCCUGACCUCAGUUCUGUGCCCCACCAAAUGCCCAGGGGCAAGAGGCCACCCUGGAAGCUGCCAAUCUUCCAAGGUGGGUGUGGGGCACGGUGGGGGCGGGCAGCUCCCAGGCCCUUGGGCAGGCUGGGGUGACGGCAGAGGCCACAGCACCAGCUCUGACAAGUCCUAUCAUCCUCUGCUCAGCAGUGACCUCCCUGGCCCCACUUUGCCCAGAGUUUGGGGUCCCCCCAGGUAUAGCUAUAGGCGGCAGUGCCUGUCCCUGGCCUGCCUUGAUUUCAGCCACACCCCUGCAGCCCUGCAUCCCAGCUCUGGGGUGUGCAGAGGUUUGUGUCUCCAGGGAACCCACGGCUGGAGAGAAAUAGGGAGAUGCAGGAAGUGGGGGCCCAUGGGGCCCCCAAGAAGCGGACUCUCCAAGGGGUACCCCCACCCCGCUACCUUCCCCACGGACGGGCCCCUCCUGGAGCCCAUACCCUCCUGUGAGGCCAUUCCAGUGUCUUCUAGAAAGACUCGCUUGCCAGGAGUGCGUUCUUUGUUGAAAAAUGCCCUGAAGCGAAAAGAUGCAGGUUUAUAUGGAACCCCCACCCCCUCCCCCACUCUCCCACUCUGUUCGUUCUGAAUGUCUUCACGAGCGUGCAUCAGGGCGCCUGGCUCCCCCACCUCAGCCAGUGAGUCAGACACGGGUUUCGCAGCCAUGUUUCCUGGCUCCGAGGACACGGGUGGCAGGCCCGUUGCAGCCCAGAGCCACUGGUCCCUACAGGGCGCCGCCACACCAGCAGGAAGGAGGAUGGCUGUGUCCGGAGCCUGGCGGGGAGGCGGCCUCCCCAGUAUGUGAGUGCAGGGAUCUGCCAGAACCACCUGGCCCUCUGUAGGGCGUUUAACUGGAAAUACCCUCACUGCCAAGUGGAGACUGGGGCGUGUGCCACAUUGCCAGCCACCAGGAAAGCUUUUCUUUUUCUUUUUUUUUUUUUUUUAAACACCAAGAGCACGUAUAGCAUGGGGGAAAGAACCUAAAUGUCUCUCUGUCCUGUGAGCUGGUGAAAAACCCAGCAUGAGAACGCAGUGUCAGGUGUGGGACUCCUUCUGCCCCUGCAGUGGGUGUUACGGGCGGUGUGCCCUGGCGAGCAAGCUUUGAUUCUUGGUUCUUUGAGCUCGUUUCAGAGGCUGAGUCCCCACAUCAGCUUUAGUUCUUGGACUUCCCUGUAUUAAGCAAGAAUUAGGAGAAUGGCUGUCCCUGCAGGCGCCUCCCGUAAAUCCUGAGCUCUCUGGCGCAAUCUGAAACUUCUCUUCUGUUUUCUUUGGCUGUAUCAGCCGAACCAGGAGAGGCCUGGGCUGCGACUAAGGAGAAAGAAAUCGGGGGUUUCUGAGAGCAGAUGGUGCCUUUGUGGGUGCAGGGCUUUUGUGGAAAUUGUCAGCCUCUACGGGCAGAGUCCGGCAUCCCCUCCCCAGACUGCCUGCUGUCAAACCACGGAGCAGCUGGAGCCUGCCCUGUCCACGGCCCGUUUCCACCCGGGCAUGUUCGUCUCUCCUGACUUCGGCAGAGGCCCCUGGUGGCCUUCAGUUUCAGUUUCUCAUCCAGGAAGGUAACCUUGGGCAUUGGCAGUGGGUUUCCCUAUGGCUUGGAUCCAGAUUAGAAUUGAUCUUUGUUUUCACUUUCCAUAGUUAAUAACAUGCAAAAUAAUGAGAAGAAUUUAUUUUAAGGUGACAGCUAUACUGGUCCAACAUCGCCUGCUUAUUGUCAGGGUACAGAAGUUUAAUACUUUCUUAAUCCAGUUUUUCAAACUUCUCCCUGUAGACCGUAAGGAUGAAUUCCACAAUAGGAUCCUUUUUAAAAUCGAUUUUAAAUUGUUGCCUAGUCCUGCCAAGGUUAUUAUGUGCAUCUGUUAUUUUUCCAAUACAUGUAAACAGUUGCAGCAUGAUGCUUUGUUUAAUGUCCUGUUCUUAAGCUCGUUAGAGCCAGUUUUGAAACGUUUGGUCUUACCGUGAACGGAGGCUGGCUUGGCUUAGCCACGCUGAUGAGUAAGUGAGGGAUGUCUCCAUCUUGAGAUCACCAGGCAAGAGAGUUGCCUGCACCAGGUAAGAGGCCAAAGCCCCUGGGGUAACAGUCCCCACCGCUACCCGAGGUAAAACAAUAAAAGCUAUGUGGUUGAGCUCAGGCCUCUCGUGCCUGGUGUCAGAGAAGGCAGAGCCCACAGUAGGUGCACGGUGCAAGGCCCUGGGAGGGCACUGGCCAGGGAAGGUGGUAUAGAUGGCCCUCAGAUUGCGGGGCCCCGAGCAGCUCCCCACUCUGCCCGUCCACCUUCCCUGGCUCCAGCCUCAUUCUCUCUUUAGUUUAACUAUGCAAAGAGAGGAGGUUGAGAGUGUUCUGGCAGCUGGAGCUCUUUUCCUUGUCCUUCCUGCCCUCCGAUGGGGCCACCUGUGUCGGGGCAGCAGUGUCCAUGUUUAUGGAGAUCAGAGGUGUCCCCACUGUGUGGCUGGACUGUACUCUGCUGCCCGGGUAGCCAGGAGUCUCUCCCUCUCUCCCCUGCCGCCUGCCUGGUCUCAUGGGCCUCCUUCACACACCCCUCCCUGUGGAUCGCCUGCCUGGGCCCAGAGCAGGGGAACUGGAGUUUGUGAGUGAGCAGAGCAGGUUAUGUGCAGACAGGGAAACGAGAACUUUGGACCUGGCUUUCUGAGUCCAGGUGAGAGCUGUGUGGCCCCCCGAUGCCACUCUGCCCGCCGGAGGGAUGUGCCUGCUGAGCCUUUUCCUUCCACGCCGCCUCUCACUGCCAGGCCAGCGGCUUCCGCUGAGACUCGCUGGAGAGGCGGCUCCCGUGUCCGUCCACCGAGCACUCAGAUGGAUGCUGAUCACCAGGGCCGAGGGGGCUCCCAGAAGGACCCCAGGCCCUGGGGAGGGUGGCUGUGGGAGGCCAAGUCCACUGCCCGGAAGUCUUGUCAGCCCUAAGCCAGGGAAGCCUGGAGCGUGGCCUGGCGGGUCUGGGUGGACACCGUCCCCACUCCGGACUCCCAGCACAGGGGAGGAUACCUGAGCCUGUAUGGCCCUGUAGCCCUGGGCAGAGCUGGGCCUGUCGUGUGUUCCUGCCUGGCAGGUGCAGGUGCUGGCCAUCUGCAGGUGGAAGGAGGUGGGAAUCUUGGAUUUUUUGUUUUUUUUUGUUUUUUUUUUUUUGAGGUGAAGUCUCGCUCUGACACCCAGGCUGGCGUGCAGUGGUGUGAUCUCGGCUCACUGCAAACUCCGCUUCCUGGGUUCAAGUGGUUCUCCUGCCCCAGCCUCCCAAGUAGCUGGGAUUACAGGCAUGCGCCACCACGCUCAGCUGAUUUUUGUAUUUUUAGUAGAGAUGGGGUUUCACCAUGUUGGCCAAGCUGGUCUCAAACUCCUGACCUCAAGUGAUCUGCCCGCCUCGGCCUCCCAGAGUGCUGGGAUUACAGGCAUGAGCCAGUGCACCCGGCGGAAUCUUGGAAUUUUUAUAGACAGCACCUCAGUUUCUGACUCCAGCCGCACACCUCCUGCCUCUGCCAGCAGGGGUUGCCGCCAGACCAGAGCCAGGGCCAGGUCCCUGCGUCCAUCCCCCCCGGUAGGAUGGACGUGAGCCAUCCUUCUAGGGGACUUUUUUCAGUGUGCGACUCGUCUCUGUUAGGUGGUAGGAGCCAGUUUGUGUGGCCUGUGCCACGCUCCACAGUGCGUGGCUGGGCUCUGUGUGUGGCCUGUGUCCCCUGUCCCUGCAGGACCCAGCAGGCAUCGUGGCGUGACAGCUGUGUCCAAGCCACUGCCCGGGCAUCCCAUCACCCACCAGGGUGCACGGUCUCUCCUGCUGGGGGCUUUCUGUCGCAUGUGUGUCUCCUGUCGACUCUGCAGUUUGUUCUCAGAGCAGAAUGUUUCCUGUUCUCAGUGCACAAAGACACUGGUUUUCAAUCGGCGUCUAAAACCACGUUCCUGCCUUUCAUUGCAACACGGUGUGUUCAUUUGUUUAAAACAGUUUAAUGAGUAAGUUUAGAUGACUGGUCAAUAUCUUAAAAAUGUAUAUUAGUAAGAAGUUCUUCCUGGAAUUUUUCUUUCGAUUCUGGCAGAAUAAACAGGUGUUUUUAGUUUUCCCACUGUCUGAGCCAAGCAGGACCCUGUCCCAGAGCAAGAGAUGUCCCCUUCCAUCUCUGACCCUUGCCUGGGACAAGCUUUGAUGGGGGGCCCCAGCUUCAAGGCUGUGGUGGGAACAGCACCCCCAAAUGCCAGCCUCUCCUUUCUUCCCAUCCACCAGUAUACUGCGGGGCCAUUUCUGGUCUUUGUCCAACAGGAAACCCAUUUCUGGUGGGAUAUGCCUUCCAGUGCCACAGGGCCACUCACCCCAUGCAUCUCUGUCCUGCCCGUCAGUGCUGGGACGGACAGCAAGGGCAAGCCCAGUGUCUGGCGGAUAGGUGGGUGGGAACAGAGAGGGGAGAAUGCCGUCCUAAGCUUCUGCUUGGGGAUCCCCCACACGACCUGGGUACUGCCUGGGAAACCUGUCCUAAGUAAAACUAUGGACCUCGCCUCGCCCACCGGCCUGCGAAGCCAGCAUCUCCGUGAAGGUGGAUGGAAGCGCCUUUGUCCUCAUUUUGAGCUGCAAGCUGGGUCAGCGGCUCUGAAGCCCUCGAGUGACUUUCUAACCCAAGACCCAGCCCCUGGCAGGAGGAGGGUGGGUGCAGGGCUGGUGGGACAAAAAGAGGCCUCAGCAGGCCUGGAAGACCCUUCCAGUACAUCCCACAGCGUGUCGAGCAGCUGGGAGAACCUGUGUCAAGCUCGAGCCGUCAUAGGUCCCCAUGAGGUGUCUGAAGCCCCUUCUUGGUGAUGGGAGGCAGAGGUGCUGACGUUCUGGAGCAUGGACGUGAGUCCUCAGCUGGCUCCGCGUGGGCCCUUGGAGGGUGCCAGGUGUGUGGUGACCUUCUGGAUGCCUUUAACUUCAUGGCUGCGUCAUUCCUGAUUUAGAACUUUAACCGGAGCUUCAUCUAGUGAUUGCAAAACUGGACCAAUGGGAGGACGGCGGCGCAGCCCGCUCCCUCCGUGGAAUGGAGCUCAGCUCUUCGGAGGCAUCAAAGCACCUGUCGCCUCCGUGGUCCCCCUGCUGAGGGAGUGCGGCCUCUGCAAGGUUCGGGGGUGGCUUCGUUUGCCUGGAGUGGCCGGCCCUGCUUGUGCCAUGUGGAUGUUUGUGAGCCUCGGUCCUACAGCACUGUGUAGGCUGCAUCUGUUUCGUGCUGGUCCUGUUGACUUGUAUGAUAUCCACAAAUAAAUAUUUUCAUGGCGGU